AGAAGGCAACAGCUCUACCAUCCUCCAAACAUCUGAAGCCCCCCAUAGAAACUCCUCUUGGAAUUGGUAAGUAUCUGUGCUCAUGGGCUUCUUCUCCAAUGAUCUGACUGUUGCUUGUACUCAUAAGGAAAUUGUUUGCCUUAUGGAUUCAUUCUCAGCACUACAAUCUCAGUGAUUAUCCCUCUGAGCUGCUCAAUUACUCCCUGUCUUUUCCUCAAUUUACCUAGGUGGUUCCCUGUCUGACCCAAAUGCUAGGCCGAUUUCAACCCUUCUCCUUGGUCCGGAGUUUCAGACUGGGAUUUGAAGCCUGCUGCUAUCCAAACCAAAAAUGUGCUACUCAGACCAUCAGACCCCCUGACUCCAGGUGCCUAGUCCAAGCAGUUUCUCAGAACUUUAAUUUUGCAAAGGAUGUGUUGGAUCAGUGGUCCCAGCUGGAAAAGGACGGACUCAGAGGGCCUUACCCCGCCCUCUGGAAGGUUAGUGCCAAAGGAGAAGAGGACAAAUGGAGCUUUGAAAGGAUGACUCAACUCUCCAAGAAGGCCGCCAGCAUCCUCUCAGACACCUGUGCCCUUAGCCAUGGAGACCGGCUGAUGAUAAUCUUGCCCCCAACACCUGAAGCCUACUGGAUCUGCCUGGCCUGUGUGCGCUUGGGAAUCACCUUUGUGCCUGGGAGCCCCCAGCUGACUGCCAAGAAAAUUCGCUAUCAAUUACGCAUGUCUAAGGCCCAGUGCAUUGUGGCUAAUGAAGCUAUGGCCCCAGUUGUAAACUCUGCCGUGUCCGACUGCCCCACCUUGAAAACCAAGCUCCUGGUGUCAGAUAAGAGCUAUGAUGGGUGGUUGGAUUUCAAGAAGUUGAUUCAAGUUGCCCCUCCAAAGCAGACCUACAUGAGGACCAAAAGCCAAGAUCCAAUGGCCAUAUUCUUCACCAAGGGUACAACAGGAGCUCCCAAAAUGGUCGAGUAUUCCCAGUAUGGUUUGGGAAUGGGAUUCAGCCAGGCUUCCAGACGGUGGAUGGAUCUCCAGCCAACAGAUGUCUUGUGGAGUCUGGGUGAUGCCUUUGGUGGAUCUUUAUCCCUGAGCGCUGUCUUGGGAACUUGGUUCCAAGGAGCCUGUGUGUUUCUGUGUCACAUGCCAACCUUCUGCCCUGAGACUGUUCUAAAUGUCCUGUCCAGAUUUCCCAUCACCACUCUAUCUGCAAAUCCAGAGAUGUACCAGGAACUGCUUCAGCACAAGUGUUUCACCAGCUACAGAUUCAAGAGUCUGAAGCAGUGUGUGGCUGCAGGAGGACCCAUCAGCCCUGGGGUGAUUGAGGACUGGAAACGCAUCACUAAGUUGGACAUCUAUGAAGGCUAUGGGCAGACGGAAACUGGUCUACUCUGUGCCACUUCCAAAACAAUAAAAUUGAAGCCAAGCUCUCUGGGGAAGCCAUUGCCACCUUAUAUUGUCCAGAUUGUGGAUGAAAACUCAAAUCUCCUGCCUCCAGGGGAAGAAGGAAAUAUUGCAAUCCGCAUAAAACUAAACCAACCUGCUUCUCUGUACUGUCCACACAUGGUAAGAAAAUUUUCUUCUUUCCUAAAUACUUUCAUUGUUGCUACUAAUCGUAGUGCCAUUAUUGUUGAGUACUUUAUGAUUUGCCAAAUACUUUUGUCCCAAUUUUUAAUUUUGCAAAUUUUUGAGUCUCCAAAAAUGUUAAAUAGUAGCACUCACCUACAUUCACUUCUUAUUAAGAUUUUGCCCCAUUUACUUCAUAUUUGCACAUUUUUGAUGAGACAUUUGGGAGUAAAUGCAGACAUUAUGACACUUUGUCCUUAA